AAAUAGACUUGUGAAUAGUUUAGUGAGCUCCCUUCUCAUGUUCCCAGCCCCUACCCUUUCAGGAGUUAUCUUGCCAUUUCUCUAUAAUUCUCUCUUUUCUUGUGUGUAUCUUUCUUCCCCCCAGACUCAUAAUACUUCCUUCUAUUUCUCUUUUUCAAGUCCUCAUUUUGUUUAGUAAUUACAGGUGUAUCAAUUAGAAUGCAAGCUCCACUAGUGUAGGGAUUUGUGUCUGUCUUGCUCACUGCUGAGUUCCCAGGACCUAGGACAGAUACCUGGCCCACACCUUACACUCCACUGCUGAAUGAAUGUUUAAUAGGCACUAAAGUUUUGAAAAUAUUAAAUGUAUUUUUCUUUUUAAUUUGUUUUUAUUUCAAUAGCUUUUGGGGUACAAGUGGUUUUUGGUUACAUGGAUGAAUUAUAUAAUGGCAAAAUCUGAGACUUUAGUGCACUCUUCGUCUGAGUAGUGUACAUUGUACCCAAUACAUAGGUUUUUACUCCCCCUCCUCCGUCCCUCUCCUUUCUGAGUCUCCAUAAUCCGUUAUAUCACUCUGUAUGCCUUUGAGUACUAAUAUCUUAGCUCCCACCUAUAAGUGAGAACAUACAGUAUUUGGUUUUCCAUUCCAUCACCUCACUUAGAAUAAUGGCCUCCAGCUCCAUUUAAGUUGCUGCAAAAGACAUUAUUUCAUUCUUUUUUUAUGGCUGAGUAAUACACCAUGGUGUAUAUAUACUACAUUUUCUUUACACAUUCAUUGGUCAAUGGGCACUGAGGUUGGUUCCCUAUCUUUACAAUUGUGAAUUAUGCAGCAAUAAACAUGUGUGUAGGUGUCUUCUUGAUAUAAUGACUUAUUUUCCUUUGGGUUGAUACCUAGUAGUGGGGUUGCUGGAUGGAAUGGUAGAUCUACUUUUAGUUAUUUAAGAAAUCUCCAUACUGUUUUCCAUAGAGGUUGUACUAAUUUGCACUCCCACCAGCAGUGUAUAAACAUUCCCUUUUCACCACGUCCAUGUUAACAUCUAUUUUUUUUUGACUUCUUAAUAAUGGCCAUUCUUGCAGGAGUAAGGUGGUAUCUCAUUGUGGUUUUAAUCUUCAUUUCCCUGAUGAUUAGUGAUGUUGAGCAUUUUUUCAGAUGUUUCUUGGCCAUUUGAAUAUCUUCUUUUGAAAUAUGUCUAUUAAUGUCAUUUGCCCACUUUUUGUGGGAUUUUUUUCUAUAAUGUUUGAGUUUCUUGUAGACGCUGGAUAUUAAUUCUUCAUUGGAUGCAUAAUUUGCAAAUAUUUUCUCCCAUUCUGUGGGUUGUCUGUUUACUCUGAUGUUUAUUUCCUUUGCUACGAAGAAGCGUUUCAGUUUAAUUAAGUCCCAUUUAUUUAUUUUUGUUUUUGUUGCAUUUGCUUUUGGGGUCUCAGUCAUGAAUUCUUUGCCUAGGCCAAUGUCCAGAAGAGUUUUUCCUAGGUUUUCUUAUAGAAUUUUUCUGGUUUCAGGUCUUAGGUUUAAAUUUUUGAUCCAUCUUGAGUUAAUUUUUGUAUAAGGUGGGAAAUAGGGAUCCAGUUUUAUUCUUUUACAUGUGGCUAACCAGUUUUCCCAGCACCAUUUAUUAAAUAUGGUGUCAUUUCCCCAAUUUAUGUUUUUGUAUGCUUUGUCAAAGAUCAGUUGGUUUUAAGUAUUUGGCUUUAUUUCUGAGUUCUCUAUUCUGUUCCAUUGGUCGAUGUAUCUACUUUUAUAACAGUAUCAUGCUGUUUUGGUAACUAUAGCCUUGUAGUAUAAUUUUAAGUCUGGUAAUGUGAUGCCUCCAGAUUUGUUCUUUUUGCUUAGGAUUGCUUUGGCUUUGCAGGCUCUUUUUUGGUUCCAUAUGAAUUUUAAGAUUUUUUUUCCAGUUCUGUGAAAAAUGAUGUUGAUAUUUGAUAAGAAUUGCAUUCAAUCUGUAGAUUGCCUUGGGCAGUGUGAUCAUUUUCAUAUUGAUUCUUCCAAUCCAUGAACAUGGGAUGUGUUUCUAUAUGUUUGUGUCAUCUAUGAUUUCUUUCAGCAGUGUUUUGUAGUUCUCCCUGUAGAAAUCUUUCAUCUCCUUGGAUAAGUAUAUUCCUAGGUAUUUUAUUUUAUUUUGUUGAAGUUGUUUUAAAAGGGAUUGAGUUCUUGCUUUGAUUCUCAGCUUGGUCACUGUAGGUGUAUAGCAGUGCUAAUUUGUGUACAUUUGAUUUUGUAACCUGAGACUUUACUGGAUUCAUUUAUCAAAUCUAGGAGUCUUCUGAAGGAGUCUUUAGGGUUUUCUAGGUAUAUGAUCAUAUAAUCAGGGAACAGUGAUACUUUGAUUUCUUUUCCAAUUUGGAUGUCAUUUAUUUCUUUCUCUUUUCUGAUUGUUCUGGCUAGGACUUCUAGUACUAUGUUGAAUAGAAGUGGUGAAAGUGGGCAUCCUUGUCUUAUUCCAGUUCUCCAGGGGAAUGCAUUAGAUUUUUUCCCAUUUAGUAUCACAUUGGCUGUGGGUUUGUCAUAUAUGACUUUUAUAACUUUGAGGUAAGCCCCUUCUAUGCCUAGUUUGUUGAGGAUCUUUAUCUAAAGGGAUGCUGGAUUUUAUCAAAUGUUUUUUCUGCAUCUAUUGAAAUGAUCUAUGGUUUUUAAUUCUGUUUUUGUGAUGUACCACAUUAUUGACUUGCAUGUGUUAAACCAUCCCUAAAUCCCUGGGAUUAAAUCCACUUGAUCAUGGUGUAUUAUAUUUUUGAUGGGCUGCUGGAUUCAAUCUCACUGUUUGUUAUUGGUCUGUUCAUGGUUUCUAUUUAUUCCCAAUUUAAUCUAGGAGGGGUGUAUGUCUCCAGGAAUUUAUUUAUUUCCUCUAGAUUUUUCUAGUUUUUGUGCAUAGAGGUGUUCAUAGUAGUCCUGAAUGAUCUUUUGUAUUUCUGUGGUGUCAGUUGUAAUGUCUCCAGUUUCAUUUCUAGUUGAGUUUAUUUGAAACUUCUCUCUUUUUUUUUGGUUACUCUGGCUAAUGUUCUAUCAAUUUUGUUUAUCUUUUCAAAGAACCAGCUUUUUGUUUAAUUGAUCUUUUUUAUUUUUUGUUUCAAUUUUAUUUCAUUCUUCUCUCAUCUUUCUUUUUUUCUGCUAGCUUUGGGUUUCUCUAGUUCCUUGAGGCAUGACAUUAGGUUGUCAAUUUGUGAUCUUUCAGACUUUUUGAUGUAGGCAUUUAGCGCUAUGAACUUUCCUCUUAAAAGCACUGCUUUUGCUGUAUCCUAGAAGUUUUGAUAAUUUAUGUCACUGUUACCAUUCAUUUCAAAUAAUUUUCUAAUUUCCGUCUUAAUUUCAGUGUUAACCCAUAAAUCAUUCAGGAGCAGAUUAUUUAAUUUCCAUUUAUUUGUUAUGGUUUUGAAAGUUCCUUUUGGAGUUGAUUUCUAGUUUUAUUCCACUGUGAUCUGAGGAGAUACUUAAUAUAAUUUCAAUUUUUUUCUUCUAAAAAACCCCCCAAAAUGGGACACACGUGCAGAACAUGCAGGUUUCUUACAUAGGUAUGCAUGUGCCAUGGUGGCUUGCUGCACCUAUUGACCCAUCCUCUAAGUUCCCUCCCCUCACCACCCACACCCCAACAGGCCCUGGUGUGUGUUGUUCCCCUCUCUGUGUCCAUGUGUUCUCAAUGAUCAACUCCCACUUAUGAGUGAGAACAUGCGGUGUUUGGUUUUCUGUUCCUGUGUUACUUUGCUGAGGAUGAUGGGUUCCAGCUUCAUCCAUGUACCUGCAAAGGACAUGAUCUUAUUACUUUUUAUGGCUGCAUAGUGUUCCAUGAUGUAUAUGUACCACAUAUUCUUUAUCCAGUCUAAAUGCUGGAUUCUUUAUCCAGCAUUUGGGUUGGUUCCACGUCUUUGCUAUGGUAAAUACUGCUGCGAUAAACAUACAUGUGCAUGUGUCUUUACAGUAGAAUGAUUUAUAUUCCUUUGGAUAUAUACCCAGUAAUGGGAUUGCUGUGUCAAAUGGUAUUUCUGGUUCUACAUCCUUGAGGAAUCACCACACUGUCUUCCACAAUGGUUGAACUAAUUUACACUCCCACCAACAGUGUAAAAGUAUUCCUAUUUCUCCACAGCCUCACCAGCAUCUAUUGUUUUCUGACUUCUUAAUAAUUGUCAUUCUGACUGGCAUGAGAUGGUCUCUCAUUGCAGUUUUGAUUUGCAAUUCUCUGAUGAUCAGUGAUGUUGAGCGUUUUUCCAUAUGUUUGUUGGCUACGUAAAUUUUUUUUUUUUUGAGAAGUGUCUGUUCAUAUCCUUUGCCCAUUUUUUGAUGGAGUUGUUUGUUUUUUUCUUGUAAAUAUGUUUAAGUUCCUUGUAAAUUCUGGAUAUUAAACCUUUGUCAGAUGGGUGGAUUGCAAAAUUUUUCUCCCAUUCUGUAGGUUGCCUGUUCACUCUAUUUCUAGUUUCUUUUGCUGUGCUGUAGCUGUUUAGUUUAAUUAAUUCCCAUUUGUCAAUCUUGGCUUUUGUUGUAAUAGCUUUUGGCUUUUUUAUCAUGAAGACUUUGCCCAUGCCUAUGUCUUGAAUGAUAUUGCUUCAGUUUUCUUCUAGGGUUUUUAUGGUUUUGGGUUUUACAUUUAAGUCUUUAAUCCAUCUUCAGUUAUUUUUUGUAUAAGAUGUGAGGAAGGGGUCCAGUUUCAGUUUUCUGCAUAUGGAUAGCCAGUUUUCCUGGCACCAUUUAUUAAAUGGGGAAUCCUUUUGCCAUUGCUUGUUUUUGUCAGGUUUGUUGAAGAACAGAUGGUUGUAGAUGUGUCGUGUUAUUUCUGAGGUCUCUGUUCUGCUCCAUGGUCUAUAUGUCUGUUUUGGUACCAGUACCGUGCUGUUUUGGUUACUGUAGCCUUGUCGUAUUGUUCAAAGUCAGGUAGUGGGAUGCAUCCCGUUUUAUCCUUUUUGCUUAGGAUUGUCCUAGCUAUAUGGGAUCUUCUUCGAUUCCAUAUGAAAUUUAAAAUAGUUUUUUUUUCUAAUUCUGUGAAGAAUGUAGAGACAAUAUACCAGAAUCUCUGGGACACAGCUAAAGCAGUGUUAAGAGGAAAACUUGUAGCACUAAAUGCCCACAUCAGGAAGCUAGAAAGAUCUCAAAUGGACACCCUAACAUCACAAUUAAAAGAGCUAGAGAGGCAAGAGCAAGCUAAUCCAAAAGCUAGCAGAAGACAAGAAAUAAGUAAGAUCAGAGAAAAAUUGAAGGAGAUAGAGACACAAAAAACCCUCAAAAAAUCAAUGAAUCCAGGAGCUGGUUUUUUGAAAAAAUUAACAAAAUAGAUCACUAGCCAUAUUAAUAAAGAAGAGAGAGAAGAAUCAAAUAGACAGAAUAAAAAUGAUAAGGGGGAAUAUCAUCACUGAUCCCACAGAAAUACAAACUACCAUCAGAGAAUACUAUAAACACCUCUACACAAAUGAACUAGAAAAUCUAGAAGAAAUGGAUAAAUUCCUGGACACAUACACCCUAUCAAGACUAAACCAGGAAGAAGUUGAAUCCCUGAAUAGACCAAUAACAAGCUCUGAAAUUGAGGCAGUAAUUAAUAGCCUACCAACAACACAAAACCCAGGACCAGAUGGAUUCACAGCUGAUUCUACCAGAAAUACAAAGAGGAGCUGGUACCAUUACUUCUGAAACUAUUCCAAACAAUUGAAAAGGAGGGAACUCCUCCUUAACUCAUUUUAUGAAGCCAGCAUCAUCCUGAUACCAAAACUGGGAAGAGACACAACAAAAAAAAAGAAAAUUUCAGGCCAAUAUCCCUGAUGAACAUCAAUACGAAAAUCCUCAAUAAAAUAAUGGCAAGCCAAAUCCAGCAGCACAUCAAAAAACUUAUUCACCAUGAUCAAGUCGGUUUCAUCUCUGAGAUGCAAGGUUGGUUCAACAUACACAAAUCAAUAAGCAUAAUCCAUCACAUAAACAGAACCAAGACAAAAACCACAUGAUUAUCUUGAUAGAUGCAGAAAAGGCCUUUGAUAAAAUUCUACAUCCCUUCAUGUUAAAAACUCUCAAUAAACUAGGUAUUGAUGGAACAUAUCUCAAAAUAAUAAGAGCUAUUUAUGACAAACCCACAGCCAAUAUCAUAUAAAAUGGGCAAAAGCUGGAAGCAUUCCCUUUGAAAACCAGUACAAGACAAGGAUGCCCUCUCUCACCAUUCCUAUUCAACAUAGUAUUAGAAGUUCUGGCCAGCACAAUCAGGCAAGAGAAAGAAAUAAAGCGUAUUCAAAUAGGAAGAGAGGAAGUCAAGUUGUUUCUGUUUGCAGAUGACAUGAUUAUAUACUUAGAAAACCCCAUCAUCUCAGCCCAAAAACUUCUCGAACUGAUAAGCAACUUCAACAAAGUCUCAGGAUACAAAAUCAAUGUGCAAAAAUCACAAGUAUGCCUUUACACCAACAAUAGGCAAGCAGAGAGCCAAAUCAUGAUGAACUACCAUUCACAAUCACUACAAAGAGAAUAAAAUACCUAGGAAUACAGCUAACAGAGGAUGGGAAGGACCUCUUCAAGGAGAACUACAAACCACUCCUCAAGGAAAUAAGAGAGGACACAAAUGGAAAAACAUUCCAUCUUCAUGGAUAAGAAGAAUCAAUAUCUUGGAAAUGGCCAUACUGCCCAAAGUAAUUUAUAGAUUCAAUGUUAUUCCCAUCAAACUAUAAUUUCAAUUUAUAAAAAUUUAUUGAGACUUGUUUUGUGGCUAUCAUAUGGUCUAUCUUGGAGAAUGUUCCAUGUGCUGAUGAGAAGAAUGUAAUCUUCUGUAAAUAUCUAUUAGGUCCAUUUGUUCUAGAGUGUAGUUUACAUCUAUUGUUUCUUUUUUGACUUUCUGUCUCAAUGAUCUCUCUGGUGCUGACAGUGGAAUACUGAAGUUCCCCACUAUUAUUGUGUUGUUGUCUUAUCUCUUUUCUUAGGUCUAGUAGUAAAUGUCUUAUGAAUCUGGGAGCUCCAGUGUUAGCUACAUCUAAAUUUAGGACUGUAAUAUCUUCCUGUUAGAUUGAUCCUUUUAUCAUUAUAUAAUGACCUUCUUUGCCUUUUUUUACUGUUGUUGCUUUAAAGUCUGUUUUAUCUGAUAUGAGAAAAGCUACUCCUGUUUACUUUUGGUUUCCAUUUGCAUGGAAUAUCUUUUUUCACCCUUAUACCUUGAAUUUAUAUGGGUCCUUGUGUGUUAAGUGAGUCUCUUGAAGAUAGCAGAUAUUUGGUUUGUGAUUUUGUAUCCAUUCUGCCAAUCUGUAUCUUUUAAGUGGAGCAUUUAGGCCCAUUUAUGUUGAACAUUAAUAUCAAGAUGUGAGGUACUGUUUCAGUCAUCAUGUUAAUUGUUACCUACAUACGUUGUUUUCUUCAUUGUGUUAUUGUUUUAUAGACCUUGUGAGUUUUAUGCUUUCAAGAGUUUGUAUUCUGGUGCAUAUCAAUCUUUCGUUUCAAGAGUUAGAACUCCUUUUGGCAUUUCUUAUAAAGCUGGUCUGGUAGUGACAAAUUCCCUCAGCAUUUGUUUGUCUAAAAAUGACUUUAUUUCUCCUUCAUUCAUAAAACUUAGCUUUGCCAGAUACAAAAUUCUUGGCUGAGAGUUAUUCUGUUUAAGGAGACUAAAGAUAAGACUCCAAUCCCUUCCAGCUUGUAAGGUUUCUGCUGAGGAAUCAUGUAUUUUUCAUCCUUGCAAAUAGUAAAGAUUUCCCUGACUAUUACAUCAAUAGGUUUCAGGGGGAGGGCAGAUGCUUGCUAGAAUUGAGAAGCCACUGCUCAGUUGGGGCCAUUUUGGCAAGCUUAGACAAAAUCUUGAAGCACAGUAUUUGUUGGGAGCAAAGAGGAAUUUAUAAAUUCCAAAAAUUACCUGUACCUAUCAAAAGAAAACUUUGGAGGUCUGAAUGUCAAGUUUUCCUAUAAGUCAUUGGUAGUGAACACUCAGCAAAUGACAGAGAGUAUGUUUCCUCCAGCCUAGGGAGGCAGUGGGGUGGGGAACUAGGAAGAAGAGGCCAGGGAGGGGAAGUGCAAGCAGGCAGAUAUGACUUUCCUUCUAGGCCAAACCCCAAGAUUGAGGCAUGCUGGGAACAAGCAGAAAAAUUAGAGGGCUUUCCAAAGCAGUGAGCCUCAUGUCCUAAUUCAUGUUUGGGAGCUGGGACAAGAUCUCUUCCCAGGCUGGCUCCCAUAAAGGUACAGAAUCCAAGAGAAUCCCCACUGACCGGCAUAUCUUAGGCCCUUUGUGAAUAAUUUUGAGUAAAAGAAUAAAGAAAAAGGGGCCAGGUGCAGGGGCUCACACCUGUAUCCGAGAACUUUGGGAGGCUAGGGCAAGAGGAUCACUUGAGGCCAGGAUUUCAAGACCAGCCUGGACAACAUAGCAAGACCUGGUCUAUACAAAAAAUUUACAAAAUAAAUUAAAAAAAGAAAAAGGGAAAAAGAAAGGAACAGAAAGGGAAGAGGGAGAGAAUACAGAGGAGAAAAAGAAAAGUGGGAUGAAGCAGAGGAACCAGAAAAAUGCAGCUUUUUUGUUUCUUAUUCUGCAAGUAACACAGUUUGUGCACUGGAGUAGACACAUGCAUGCAGGCAUGCAAGCAAGCAUGGGUUGACUGAGGUAGUUCUGAACACUCUAUGACUCCAAAUCUAAUCCAGUUUGGAACUGAAAGUCUGAAUCCUGCUUGGGGAUUUAGGUUUCUUGUGUCUAUUCUUCUGGGCUCUGACCCUAGACAGGAAACAAUUCUAAUCUCAAAAUUGUCUGAUGCCUCAUGUCCACCUCAACCCCAUUCCCUCCCUAUGAUAAGAGAAAAGAAGACUAGGUAUAAACCAAGUUGGUGUUAGGUUUGCUCUUCCUUUGUUGGGGAGUCUACUGAUGGGGUGGCCUAGGGGACAAGGUUGGGGCUGGCUGUGCUCCAGGCACAUGUGGCUGGAGAGGAGGUCAUGCCAGCUGGUCAGGUGAGGGGCCUGAUAAACACCAAGAGAGUAACAAUUUCACUUUUCUUCCUUAUGUCUUGGGCAUUUUUUUUUUCUGUUUUCUUUUUGAACUUGGCCAUAUUCUUUUCUCCUUUUUUCUAAAAAAGAAAAAACCCACAUCUUUUAUGGCUACAAAUAUUGAUCUACAAACCUGCAAUGUCAUUACUUUUUUAAGUAAUUUUUUUCCUGUUUUCCCUGACUUUGAGAAGGCAAGAAAACCAUGUGACCUAUGUGAAAAAAGUACUCCAUUUUAGCUGGAAAUUGAAUUAGGGGAUUGAAUAAAGAUGGAUCAGGAAUAUACUAGAGGACUAACAUUUAAUAUAUGUCAUUUAAAAAGUUUUUUGGGGACAGAGUCUUGUUCUGUUAUGCAGGCUGGAGUGCAGUGGCAUAAUCUCAGCUCACUGCAAUCUCCACAUCCUGGGUCCAAGUGAUUAUCGCACCUCAGCCUCCUGAGUAGCUGGCAUAACAGGUAUGCACCCCCAGGCUAACUUUUGCAUUUUUAGUAGAGACGGGGUUUCACCAUGUUGGCCAGGCUGGUCUUGAACUCCUGGACUCAAGUGAACCUCCUGCCUCAGCCUCCCAAGGUGCUGGGAUUACAGGCAUGAGCCGGCAUGCCUUAUUAAUUUUAAAAUUAAUAAGCAGUUUUUCAAGACUAGACAAAGAUUGUUAUAAACCAUGGAUAUUAAAAGGUUUCCUAGCCAAAAUUCAGGGCCAGAAAUUACACAGUUAUGAGAUAAACAGAUUUGAAUGUUUAAAAAAUUAAAAAUAUACAGAAGGAGCAGGACUGAAAAAAACUGUUCACAGUUCAAAAAACACCCCGACACUAUUAAAGCAAAAACAAAAUUUAAAUAUACAUAGCAUAUAGAAGGUUAAUAUCCUUAUUAGAUAAAGCAAAAGAUGAAUGGUAAUCUAGGAAAAUAAGCAAAAAAUAUAAGUUAAAAAUGCUCAAGGAGGAAAUGAAGAUGACAAAUUUAUUUAGAAAUCAUCUCUAUAUUACUACUAAUCAAAGAAACUCAUUGUUUGGAUGUUAAGGAUACCUAAACAUUUAAAAAGUUUUAUUACAUCCAGCAUUGAGGAUGUAGGAAAUGAAUACUCAUAUAUUGUUAAAGGGAAUAUAAAUCAUUAUGUUUUCUGGACAGCAAAUUGGUAACAUGUAUAAUUAAGAUAUAGAUUUUAACCAAGUAAGCUUGUGUUUAAGAAUCAAUUCUAAGGAAAUUAUUGGACAAGUGUGCAAAGAUACAAAUACACACAAACCUGAUUUCUAUUUUCAUAUAAAAAUAAGAAAUAAACUGUCCACUAGUAGGUGAUUAUUUAAACAAAUUGCGGUGAAUCAUACGUAACGUGCCAUGCAGUUAAAAAAAUAGAUAACAUUGAUACAGAGAUGAUACACAAUGAAAAAAGUGAUUUAUAGAAUAGACUAUAUAGUAUGAGCUUAUAUAUAAAAAGAAAAAUGUAUGCAUACUUAUACAAAAAUAAAGUGGGGGAAGCAGAUUAAAUAGAUGUUUAACUUUAUGAUUUAUAAUUUUCUUUUUUUUAAAAUUUUAUUAUUAUAUUUUAAGUUUUAGGGUACAUGUGCACAAUGUGCAGGUUUGUUACAUAUGUAUACAUGUGCCAUGUUGGUAUGCUGCACCCAUUAACUCGUCAUUUAGCAUUAGGUAUAUCUCCUAAUGCUAUCCCUCCCUCCUCCCCGCACCCCACAACAGUCCCCAGAGUGUGAUGUUCCCCUUCCUGUGUCCAUGUGCUCUCAUUGUUCAAUUCCCACCUAUGAGUGAGAACAUGCAGUGUUUGGUUUUUUGUCCUUGCAAUAGUUUGCAGAGAAUGAUGGUUUCCAGUUUCAUCCAUGUCCCUACAAAGGACAUGAACUCAUCAUUUUUUAUGGCUGCAUAGUAUUCCAUGGUGUAUAUAUGCCACAUUUUCUUAAUCCAGUCUAUCGUUGUUGGACAUUUGGGUUGGUUCCAAGUCUUUGCUAUUGUGAAUAGUGCCACAAUAAACAUACGUGUGCAUGUGUCUUUAUAGCAGCAUGAUUUAUAAUCCUUUGGGUAUAUACCCGGUAAUGGGAUGGCUGGGUCAAAUGGUAUUUCUAGUCCCAGAUCCCUGAGGAAUCACCACACCGAUUUCCACAAUGGUUGAACUAGUGUACAGUCCCACCAACAGUGUAAAAGUGUUCCUAUUUCUCCACAUCCUCUCCAGCACCUGUUGUUUCCUGACUUUUUAAUGAUUGCCAUUCUAACUGGUGUGAGAUGGUAUCUCAUUGUGGUUUUGAUUUGCAUUUCUCUGAUGGCCAGUGAUGAUGAGCAUUUUUUCAUGUGUUUUUUGGCUGCAUAAAUGUCUUCUUUUGAGAAGUGUCUGUUCAUAUCCUUCGCCCACUUUUUGAUGGGGUUGUUUGUUUUUUUCUUGUAAAUUUGUUUGAGUUAAUUGUAGAUUCUGGAUAUUAGCCCUUUGUCAGAUGAGUAGGUUGCGAAAAUUUUCUCCCAUUUUGUAGGUUGCCUGUUCACUCUGAUGGUAGUUUCUUUUGCUGUGCAGAAGCUCUUUAGUUUAAUUAGAUCCCAUUUGUCAAUUUUGUCUUUUGUUGCCAUUGCUUUUGGUGUUUUAGACAUGAAGUCCUUGCCCAUGCCUAUAUCCUGAAUGGUAUUGCUUAGGUUUUCUUCUAGGGUUUUUAUGGUUUUAGGUCUAACAUGUAAGUCUUUAAUCCAUCUUGAAUUAAUUUUUGUAUAAGGUGUAAGGAAGGGAUCCAGUUUCAGCUUUCUACAUAUGGCUAGCCAGUUUUCCCAGCACCAUUUAUUAAAUAGGGAAUCCUUUCCCCAUAUAAUUUUCUUUUUCUUUGUUUUGAGACAGGGUCUUACUACAUUGUCAAGCUGGUUUCAAACUCCUGGGCUCAAGCAAUUCUCCCAUGUUGGCCUCCCAAAGUGCUGGGAUUACAGGUGUGAGCUACCAUGCCUAGCCUGAUUUACAAUUUUCUACACUGAAGAUUUUAUUAGGAAUAUUGUAUCACACAAGACAGGGUAGGCUGUGCUGCAGUAACAAAUGAAACCAAAUUUUGGUGGUUUAACAUUGAAAAGUGUAUUUCUCUAUCACAUGAAGUUCUCUGUAGGACAAUAGGACCCUCUGUAGGACUGGAAGUCCUCUGUAGGGCCCUCCAGGGCUGCUGUCCUCUAUGUGGUAGGUCAUGCUGCUUUGGCCUUCUGGCGCCUCCCUCUUCCACACACUUCCACAGGCGGGAAAAGAAUGUGGAGAGCUGCAAUGGGCUCUUACAUGCUGUGACCCAGAAGUGACACCCAUCUCUCUGGCUUAUUUGCCAGAGCUAGUAUAGCAGAGCUGCCUCCUGCAAGGGGGAUGAUAAUGGAGCUUUCCAAGUGUCUGGGAAGGGGAGAAGAAUUGGAACUAGAGGAGGGCAGUCAUAAUGCCCACCAUAAACAUGGGCAGGGUGAGCACUGCUAGUUGUUCCUCUUUCUCUGGUCUCCCUUUUUCUUUAGUAAUAAAGCCCCUGAUUCUGAGCCCCUUAUUCUUAUAGAUUAAAGAUUACAUUUCCCAGCCUCCUUUGAAGUCAGGUGUGGCCGUGCAACCAGUCCUGGCAAUAAAAUGAUAGAAUUUUUUUUUCUUUUUUGAGAUGGAGUCUUGCUCUGUUGCCCAGGCUGGAGUGCAGUGGCAUGAUCUUGGCUCACUGCAACCUCUGCCUCCUGGGUUCAAGCAAUUCUCCUGUCUCAGCCUCCUGAGUAGCUGGGAUUACAGGUGCACACCACCAGGCUCAGCUAAUUUUUUUUGUAUUUUUAGCAGAGAUGGGGUUUCACCAUGUUGGCCAGACUGGUCUUGAACUUCCAACCUGAAGUGAUCCACCCACCUCGGCCUCCCAAUAGCAAAUUAUUAAUGAUAGCAAAUUACUAUCUGUGACCGGAAGCAUUUAGAGUCCUUCAGUGGAGGAGGUGUGCCCUUCUUUGACUUUGCCAUUUUCUCUUUAGCUGGAACAUAGACAUGCUGGCUGGACCUCAAUAAAGGGGAUGCCACAUGCUGAGGAUGAUGGAGCCACAUGCUGAGGAUGAUGGAGCAACAAGCAAGAAUAAGCCCAGGACCCUACAGUAAGUAAAUGGUCUCAACCAGUGAAUGGAAAAAGGAAAGUAACUUCAAAUUUUGGAAAGGGAUUCAGAACAAAAUCAUCAGGUUGAAGAUCCCGGAAGAUGACUGAAGCUCAGCCAGGGGGAAGCCUUUUGAUGGUGAAGUGUCAGAGAGCAAAGGAGGAACUGUCAACAAUGGUGAUUCCACUAAUGAAAAUAUCCAAUGUGAGCUGGUGGUCCUUUGCUUGUUGUUCUGAGGAUGGUCGCAGAGAUCCAGAACGUAGAGGGUCAGAACCUGCAGGAGCAGGUUUGCCCUGAGCCCAUUUUCAGGUUCUUCAGAGAAAACAAGGUGGAGAUUGCAAGUGCAAUAACAAGGCCAUUUCCUUUCCUUAUGGGCCUCCGAGACCGCUCCUUCAUCUCCGAGCAGAUGUAUGAACAUUUUCAAGAAGCUUUUAGAAACCUGGUCCCAGUGACAAGAGUGAUGUAUUGUGUACUCAGUGAACUGGAGAAGACAUUUGGCUGGUCACAUCUGGAAGCAUUGUUCAGCAGGAUUAACCUGAUGGCCUAUCCUGAUUUAAACGAGAUUUACAGAAGCUUCCAGAAUGUAUGCUAUGAACACUCACCUCUCCAAAUGAAUAAUGUAAACGAUUUAGAAGAUAGACCCAGAUUACUACCAUAUGGUAAACAAGAGAACAGCAAUGCCUGUCAUGAAAUGGAUGAUAUAGCAGUGCCUCAGGAAGCCUUGAGCUCCUCGCCAAGGUGUGAGCCAGGUUUCUCUUCAGAGUCUUGUGAGCAGUUAGCUCUCCCAAAGGCUGGUGGAGGAGAUGCUGAAGAUGCACCCAGCCUACUACCAGGUGGGGGAGUGUCCUGUAAACUUGCUAUACAAAUAGAUGAAGGAGAAUCAGAAGAAAUGCCCAAGUUACUGCCUUAUGAUACAGAAGUUCUAGAAAGCAACGGGAUGAUAGAUGCGGCAAGGACAUACAGCACAGCACCAGGGGAGAAACAGGGAGAGGAGGAAGGCAGGAACAGUCCCAGAAAAAGAAACCAAGACAAGGAGAAGUACCAAGAGAGUCCAGAGGGAAGAGACAAAGAGACCUUUGAUCUAAAAACUCCCCAAGUCACUAAUGAAGGAGAACCAGAGAAGGGGCUCUGUCUACUACCAGGUGAAGGAGAAGAGGGCAGUGAUGACUGUUCAGAAAUGUGUGAUGGAGAAGAGCCCCAGGAAGCCUCUAGCUCCCUAGCAAGAUGUGGGUCAGUUUCUUGUUUAUCUGCAGAGACCUUUGAUCUAAAGACUCCCCAAGUCACUAAUGAAGGAGAACCAGAGAAGGAGCUCAGUCUACUACCAGGUGAAGGAGAAGAGGGCAGUGAUGACUGUUCGGAAAUGUGUGAUGGAGAAGAGCGCCAGGAAGCCUCUAGCUCCCUAGCAAGACGUGGGUCAGUGUCUAGUGAACUAGAAAAUCACCCAAUGAAUGAAGAAGGAGAAUCAGAAGAGCUUGCUUCUAGCCUGCUAUAUGAUAAUGUACCAGGAGCGGAGCAAUCAGCAUAUGAAAAUGAGAAGUGUUCCUGUGUCAUGUGUUUCUCAGAAGAGGUGCCAGGAAGCCCAGAAGCAAGGACGGAAAGUGAUCAAGCGUGUGGCACAAUGGAUACUGUGGAUAUUGCAAACAACUCCACUUUGGGAAAACCCAAGAGGAAAAGAAGAAAAAAGAGGGGGCAUGGCUGGAGCAGAAUGAGAAUGAGAAGGCAGGAAAACAGCCAACAAAAUGAUAAUAGCAAAGCCGACGGCCAGGUGGUCUCCAGUGAAAAGAAGGCGAACGUGAAUCUGAAAGACCUUUCCAAGAUUAGGGGGAGAAAGAGAGGCAAACCUGGAACCCGCUUCACUCAGAGUGACAGAGCUGCACAGAAAAGAGUCCGAUCAAGAGCUUCAAGAAAGCACAAAGAUGAAACUGUGGAUUUUAAGGCUCCUUUGCUUCCAGUGACCUGUGGUGGGGUGAAGGGAAUUUUACAUAAGAAGAAAUUGCAGCAAGGAAUCUUGGUGAAGUGUAUACAGACUGAGGAUGGAAAAUGGUUCACCCCCACGGAAUUUGAAAUCAAAGGAGGCCAUGCAAGAUCAAAGAACUGGAGGCUGAGUGUGCGCUGUGGCGGGUGGCCCCUACGAUGGCUGAUGGAGAAUGGAUUUCUGCCUGAUCCUCCAAGAAUACGUUACAGGAAAAAAAAGAGAAUACUGAAGUCUCAAAACAAUAGCUCAGUUGACCCUUGUAUGAGAAACCUGGAUGAGUGUGAGGUGUGCCGGGACGGAGGGGAGCUGUUCUGUUGCGACACUUGUUCAAGAGUCUUCCAUGAGGACUGUCACAUCCCGCCUGUGGAAGCUGAGAGGACCCCGUGGAAUUGCAUCUUCUGCAGGAUGAAGGAGUCUCCGGGAAGCCAACAGUGUUGUCAGGAAUCUGAGGUCCUGGAGAGGCAGAUGUGUCCUGAGGAACAGUUGAAAUGUGAGUUCCUCCUCUUGAAAGUCUAUUGCUGUUCUGAGAGCUCCUUUUUUGCCAAGAUUCCAUACUAUUAUUAUAUUAGAGAGGCGUGUCAAGGCCUGAAGGAGCCCAUGUGGUUGGAUAAAAUCAAGAAAAGGCUGAAUGAGCACGGUUACCCCCAAGUGGAGGGGUUUGUACAAGACAUGCGCCUCAUCUUCCAGAACCACAGGGCCUCUUACAAGUACAAGGAUUUUGGCCAAAUGGGAUUUAGACUGGAGGCUGAGUUUGAGAAGAAUUUCAAGGAAGUGUUUGCUAUUCAGGAAACAAAUGGGAACAAUUGACUGGAUUAGUGGAUGCUGAAAGCAUUCAGCAAAUGGCACCCUAAAAUAUGCCGCUGGUUUGCCACUGACUUCAAAAUGAGGUCACUUGGGCACAGCACAUGCAGGGAGGGGCUUUUCUCUGAGCCUCCUUCAUCUGCCCAAAGACAAAUCCUCAAAAGGAAAUUCAAUCAUCAUGAAUCACAACCCCAAGUAUCUCAUCAGCCAGGGAAGAGUAAGUGGGAUCACAGGGAAGGAUGUUGGCAGCGACACCAUCCCAUACAGGCUCUUACCUCUUCUCCUGAGGGCUGCUCCAGACAACAUUUAUUACCCAGAAGACCUUUUGUCUGAAAACCAGCCAAGCUUUAUUCAGGACACACUUCUUGCCUUCACUUUCCCACUUCCGUGGCCACCUCCAUGCAGAAGCCCUAAGCCCACAUUCUUUCGAUAGCUCACGGUGGUGCAUGAGUGUCCAUCAUCUGACUCUUCUCGGAGUCUCAUAUUUUGUGGGACUCCUGUGCAAACAUAUGUUAUUAAAAUUUUUUUCCUCCUGUU